GCAGAACCCAGGAAGGGAGCAGAGGCGAGAGCCAGCCUCCGGCAGGAGGGCGUAGACCCCGGUGCCAGCCAGAACGGCUCCAGCCUUCCCGCGGCCAGAGAGCCAGCGGCGGGAGGGGACGGGCGGGACCUCCGCGGACAGCCCCGGGUGCGGACCAGCGGGCAGCGGCCGGCGAGACCCUCCCUGGAUCCGCCCAGAGCUUACCGGACCCUGCGCGCCCCCGUCCCGGCUCCCGGCCGGCUCGGGGGAGAAGGCGCCCGAGGGGAGGCGCCGGACAGAUCGCGUUUCGGAGGCGGCGCAGUAAGAAGAAUUGAAAAAUAAUUCACAGAGAAUUGAUUCCCAUGAUGCGUUCACCUAUGUCCUGCUCAGAACACAUCUAGGAUCAUUUCAGCGCUGAUAGACUGUUCAAGGAGAUGCAGCCUAACUCAAGAAAAAUUCAUCAUGCUCCUCCUCUUUCCUUCUCCAGUUUUGUUCCCACAUAUGAACAUUAAAUGAAAAUUUAUGAAGUUCCUGCUGAGUGAAAAUCACUGCUGGAUAGGUGAAUUCCAAGAUGAAAUAGAUAGACUUUCUGGCCUGAAGUUGCUUACUGUUACCACUGAAUAUAUGCCCAUAAAAUAUUAAAAUAGACCUAAAUGCCUUUUCUGAGGUCUGGAACUCUCAAAGUGUUGUGAGCCUCCAAUCUAAUUAAAGAACUCACUCAAGUAUAAUGCAAAAUAGAGGAUGAAAAAUGCCAUACGAAUGUAUAGAUAAUGUUUUAUGGGAGAUUAGAAUAGAGAAAGAUUAUUUCCAGCUUGUGCACUGUUAAAAGUCAUUAGGAAAGAGGUAGAAUUUGGAAAGCAAAGAAGAGAUUGCAUUGCAAAGAAGACAUUCAAUUGCAAUGAUUAUUUCUCUGAAGCAAAAUAAGUGUUCAAGCCCAAUUUAAUGAGCAAUUAAUUUUUAGCAAUAUUUUCCACAUGUUCAUAAUCUAGUACCAUUUGAAAAAACUUUCUGAUGUGAAAAAAAUGUGAUUUAAAUACCUGUCUCAAGUUCUGAAAGGCUUCCUCACAUAUUAUAAAACAGGAGCCCUCCCUAAUUUGAGUCAGGUUAGAGAAAGCCAAACAUAGGUGGAAUAUGGAUACCUUUACUACAACUACAUUUGGGGAGUCAACCUAAUGCUUGCUUAAUCGCUUCACAGAAAGAUUGAGGAAGGCAGUGAUAUCCAGUAUCAUCAUAGGGCUCUUUGGUGCCAAUAAUCUAUUGAGGUGCUUUUCGAUUGUGAGACGACCAAGAAAUUAGCUGAUCCCAGCAGAAAAACAGAGCUCCUUCCUUACUUUUCAGCUGCGUUAAUUUCUUCUCUACGUUUCAGAGUACUGCUAAUUCCAUCCACUGAUCCCUUCUAGGGCCUGGUUUUCAGUCCUAGGCACUCAGGUAAGGCUAUUCUCUAGACACAAUAUGCAUGUGAAACAAAAAAAGAGAAAAGUAAUAAUGACUUCAAAUAUUAGGAUCUGACUAUGAAAUAUCAGAUCUUUUAACUCUUGUAUUCAUGUAACCUUCCUACAUUUUUCAAGUGAAAAUAUUUCCUACAUUUUUUAAGAGACAUCAGUGUUACGUGCUACGUUAUCAAUAUUAUUUUCUUAUUGGCCAUGGAAAUGCUUAAAUAAUUGACUUGACUUGUUAAAUCUAUUUUAUACAUUGCAUUUUAAUUACAUUUAUAAUUUUAAGAAACUUCACUUUUUAGAAAGAUAUAGACAUGAAUACCCUUGGUAUUAAUUAGUAGUAGAUGUCCUUACUUCUGAUAGCCCUUACAUAAUGUAUCCCUCUCUAUGAGUGCUGUAGAUUUUUCACUUAUAUCUACAAAUACAGAAGAUAUAACUUAUUAAAAGUUCAAUAGGAAUAAGUCCUCAUGUUAUGAGAGAGUAUAAAGCAAUAGUUAGAGUGAUGUGAAAUAUUAUAACUCUGUCUUCUGGAAUUAUUCCUUGAAAAGAUUAAUUAUGUAUGCCUAAUGAGAUAACAGUGACAAGGUAUAAUUUAGAGAUUAUAAAGCUGAGAAUUGAAAUGCCUAGCAUGUGCACGUGCACACACACACACACACACACACACACGUAACUGCUCUUUUGCAAAUCUUCAUCACAUCAAUUGUGUUGAAUCCAUUCUCUUAGGCUAUACAUUCUCAUGCUAGCAAAAUGAAAACUUGAAAGUAAUAUGUUGAAGAGAUACUAUGUUGAAGAGAUUCCCAUGUUGAUUGCAGCAUUAUUUACAAUAGCCAAGAUAUAGAAUCAACCUAAGUGUCCAUCAACAGAUGAAUAAAGAAAAUGUGGUGUAUAUAUACACAAUUGAAUAGUACUCAGCCAUAAUAAGAAUGAAAUCCUGUCAUUGUGGUAACAUGGAUGAAUCUAGAGGACAAUAUGCUAAGUGAAAUAAGCAAGGCACAGAAAGACUAAUAUCCCACGUUCUCACUCAUUUGUGGAGUCUGAAAAAGCUGAUGUCACAAAAGUACAGAGUUAUUAGUGACUCCGGAAUGUAUCAAGGAGGGGAGGAUAGGAAGAGAUUGGUCAAUGACAUAAAAUUACAAUUAGACAGGAGAAAUAAGUUCUGGUGUUCUAUAGCAUAGUUGGGUGACUAUAGUAAACAGUAUUAUAGUUUGUAUUUCCAAAUAACUAGAAGAGAGGAUCCUGAGUUCUCACCACAAAGAAAUAAUGUUUCAGGAGACGGAUAUGCGAAAGCCAAUGUACACAUGUAUCCAAUCAUUAUGAUGUACUCCAUAGAUGUGUGUACUUAUUGUGUAUCAAUUAAAAACACAAUUCAAAAAUUGUCAUGGGUUUGCUCUUUUUUUUUGCAUUACAAAGUGACAUCUAUUUCUUGACUACAUGCUAGGUGAUUAAUUAUAAAAUGGCUCUGUGCAUUGAAGCAUCUCUUUCAAGAGCUUUACAACCUGACUUUUGGGAAAGAUACAUUGUAUCUUUUGAAUGAUUCAAUAGUGAAAUUUAUUUCUGAGUUUACCAUUUUGUGAUUUCUGAAUUUUUUCACUUUCAGCAUUUCCACUAGUGUUUUAUUUACUGGUUCCACAAAUCAGUCAGUUUCAUCAAAUUUGCCAACUGCAAGCCUAAACCAUUGGAAAUUGGCAUAAUGAAUGUUCUGAGUGAGAAUAUAUAUGUUAUUAGGAAUAUUUUAAAUAUAAGAAAAUGUGAUACAAACCUGGCUGCCAAAAUAUGGCAAAAAUGUAAACAAAAAUUGAUGUGUAAAAAAUACCACUGUAUUUAAAAGGGAUAAAACUAAUCAGAUAGUAUUUUAAAGCUGAUGUCUUGAUGGCACAAUUUUAAAUUGAAGUGCUAUGGGGGAUAUUGUCUUACUGGUAUUUGCAGUUUGGGCUCAAAAAACCAGAAACUAUAUCUUUAAGGGUGUUUAACAGAAUAAUUCUAAAUAUUAUAGUUUUCUCUUUCCUUUUUGUUGUCCUGUGAUUUUAACUUUGACAUUCUUAUGUGACAAUUGAAAAAGUCUCUUCACUUUUGUGUAUUCUUUCUAAUGUGAUCAGGAGAAUUAAAAUGAACAUUUUCUUUCAUAAAGCUGAGAGUUAAUUCUGAAACGUUGUACCAGAAUACUUUUAUGAAUGAAAGACUAGCCUUUGAACCCUAGGAGAGUCAACUCUACACCAACCCUGUCUAUUAAAAAAAGUCUGUGCUUACAGAUGUCUUGUGUGAGAUGUGGCUUUACCAAAAGUAUCUGAACUUCAAAUUUCUCCUAUCACUGCCAACUACCCAUGGGUAUUGGCAAUAUAUUUGGUAGACUUAUUUCUUCUGUAGGCAUAUGAUGCCAUGGCCAAAGUGAACUCUACAUUUUUAAGAGAGGCUGCUAAAUAUGGCCAAUCACAACAGAAAACUAGCAUUUCUCCAAUUUGGCAGUGGUUUCUGGAUGGCACACCCAGACUUACUUCCUUAAGCAAUGCUGAUAUAUGGAAAUGCCAUGAUAGAGGCUCAGAAGCUAACACUGAAUUCAGCAGUGCAGAAAAACUCCAAAUCAUGUGGUUCUUCUUUGUCAAUAUUUUCACUAAGGCAGCAUAAGAUAUUAAAUCACCUGGAAUUAGUUAUGUGCCAUUUCAGCAACCUUUUGUGCUCAGUCUGCUACAAGCUGCUUGUGCUGAUUAGCAGUUUAAAAGUCUGCAGGGGAAGGAAAUUUUCAGUAGCUUGAUUUUCCCCCACCCUUUGGUCCUGUGUGCAUUGGGGAAGAAAUUACCUUCUGUGCAAUUCCUGAAUAAUUUGGUUUGAUUAUUAAUAGAUUCAUGCUGAAAAAAGAACAAUAACAGAAAAAAAAUUACCCAUGGGGUUGCAGCUGUGCUCCCAGAUACAAAACAGGGAAAGAAAACAGGUCUCUCCAAGCAAAGGGUAUAUGUGUAUACGUGUGUGUGCAUGUGUAGCUCUGAUUCUAAGAAGCCAUUGGUUCAUUUAUUCAUGCAUCAAAUAUUUAUUGAGCUGCGAACAAAUCCCAGGCACUGUGAGGAAGACAGAUUUCCUGCCCUCCCAGAGUUGCCAUUACUAAGAAUGUUAGCCAAUAAAUAAAUCUUUACGGGAAAGAAACAAAGGACUGUGAUAGAAAAAAAUGGGAGGAGAAACUUACUUUAGAAAGGAUUAUCUGAGAAGGUGCCUUUCACGCUGAGCCAGAAAGGGAAGAAGGCAAACAGGAAAAGAGCCAGAAGAGCAGAGUUCCCAGCAGAGGGGAAGCAAGUGGAGAGGCGGUGUGGAGGAAUCAAUUUGGCCCCAUCUGGAAUGGACAGAAGGCUAGAACCUGCAGUGCAGUGAGUGUGGGAGAAACCAGCUGGCACAAGGUGCUGUAAACUGCAAACCAUAAUCCUGUCUUAAUACUGCAAACAAAUCAUAGUGGAACUAAGGGGAACUUAAUUUACUGUUUCCAGGUUAACUAAGGUCUCAGCUGUAAACCAAAAGUGAGAGGAGACAUUAAGAUUUUCAUUCUUACCGGGUUGUCUUCUUCCUGAAGAGCAAUGGAGCCGCUUUUACUUGGAAGAGGACUAAUCGUAUAUCUAAUGUUCCUCCUGUUAAAAUUCUCAAAAGCAAUUGAAAUACCAUCUUCAGUUCAACAGGUUCCAACAAUCAUAAAACAGUCAAAAGUCCAAGUUGCCUUUCCCUUCGAUGAGUAUUUUCAAAUUGAAUGUGAAGCUAAAGGAAAUCCAGAACCAACAUUUUCGUGGACUAAGGAUGGCAACCCUUUUUAUUUCACUGACCAUCGGAUAAUUCCAUCGAACAAUUCAGGAACAUUCAGGAUCCCAAACGAGGGGCACAUAUCUCACUUUCAAGGGAAAUACCGCUGCUUUGCUUCAAAUAAACUGGGAAUCGCUAUGUCAGAAGAAAUAGAAUUUAUAGUUCCAAGUGUUCCAAAAUUCCCAAAAGAAAAAAUUGACCCUCUUGAAGUGGAGGAGGGAGAUCCAAUUGUCCUCCCAUGCAAUCCUCCCAAAGGCCUCCCACCUUUACACAUUUAUUGGAUGAAUAUUGAAUUAGAACACAUCGAACAAGAUGAAAGAGUAUACAUGAGCCAAAAGGGAGAUCUAUACUUCGCAAACGUGGAAGAAAAGGACAGUCGCAAUGACUACUGUUGCUUUGCUGCAUUUCCAAGAUUAAGGACUAUUGUACAGAAAAUGCCAAUGAAACUAACAGUUAACAGUUUAAAGCAUGCUAAUGACUCAAGUUCAUCCACAGAAAUUGGUUCCAAGGCAAAUUCCAUCAAGCAAAGAAAACCCAAACUGCUGUUGCCUCCCACUGAGAGUGGCAGUGAGUCUUCAAUUACCAUCCUCAAAGGGGAAAUCUUGCUGCUUGAGUGUUUUGCUGAAGGCUUGCCAACUCCACAGGUUGAUUGGAACAAAAUUGGUGGUGACUUACCAAAGGGGAGAGAAACAAAAGAAAAUUAUGGCAAGACUUUGAAGAUAGAGAAUGUCUCCUACCAGGACAAAGGAAAUUAUCGCUGCACAGCCAGCAAUUUCUUGGGAACAGCCACUCACGAUUUUCACGUUAUAGUAGAAGAGCCUCCUCGCUGGACAAAGAAGCCUCAGAGUGCUGUGUAUAGCACCGGAAGCAAUGGCAUCUUGUUAUGUGAGGCUGAAGGAGAACCUCAACCCACAAUCAAGUGGAGAGUCAAUGGCUCCCCAGUUGACAAUCAUCCAUUUGCUGGUGAUGUUGUCUUCCCCAGGGAAAUCAGUUUUACCAACCUUCAACCAAAUCAUACUGCUGUGUACCAGUGUGAAGCCUCAAAUGUCCAUGGAACUAUCCUUGCCAAUGCCAAUAUUGAUGUUGUGGAUGUCCGUCCAUUGAUACAAACCAAAGAUGGAGAAAAUUACGCUACAGUGGUUGGGUACAGUGCUUUCUUACAUUGCGAGUUCUUUGCUUCACCUGAGGCAGUCGUGUCCUGGCAGAAGGUGGAAGAAGUGAAACCCCUGGAGGGCAGGCGGUAUCAUAUCUAUGAAAAUGGCACAUUGCAGAUCAACAGAACCACCGAAGAAGAUGCUGGGUCUUACUCAUGUUGGGUAGAAAAUGCUAUAGGAAAAACUGCAGUCACAGCCAAUUUGGAUAUUAGAAAUGCUACAAAACUUAGAGUUUCUCCUAAGAAUCCUCGUAUCCCCAAAUUGCAUAUGCUUGAAUUACAUUGUGAAAGCAAAUGUGACUCACAUUUGAAACACAGUUUGAAGUUGUCCUGGAGUAAAGAUGGAGAAGCCUUUGAAAUUAAUGGCACAGAAGAUGGCAGGAUAAUUAUUGAUGGAGCUAAUUUGACCAUAUCUAAUGUAACUUUAGAGGACCAAGGUAUUUACUGCUGUUCAGCUCAUACUGCUCUAGACAGUGCUGCCGAUAUAACUCAAGUAACUGUUCUUGAUGUUCCGGAUCCACCAGAAAACCUUCACUUGUCUGAAAGACAGAACAGGAGUGUUCGGCUGACCUGGGAAGCUGGAGCUGACCACAACAGCAAUAUUAGCGAGUAUAUUGUUGAAUUUGAAGGAAACAAAGAAGAGCCUGGAAGGUGGGAGGAACUGACCAGAGUCCAAGGAAAGAAAACCACAGUUAUCUUACCUUUGGCUCCAUUUGUGAGAUACCAGUUCAGGGUCAUAGCCGUGAACGAAGUAGGGAGAAGUCAGCCUAGCCAGCCGUCAGACCAUCAUGAAACACCACCAGCAGCUCCAGAUAGGAAUCCACAAAACAUAAGGGUUCAAGCCUCUCAACCCAAGGAAAUGAUUAUAAAGUGGGAGCCUUUGAAAUCCAUGGAGCAGAAUGGACCAGGCCUAGAGUACAGAGUGACCUGGAAGCCACAGGGAGCCCCAGUGGAGUGGGAAGAAGAAACAGUCACAAACCACACAUUGCGGGUGAUGACGCCUGCUGUCUAUGCCCCUUAUGAUGUCAAGGUCCAGGCUAUCAAUCAACUAGGAUCUGGGCCUGACCCUCAGUCAGUGACUCUCUAUUCUGGAGAAGACUAUCCUGAUACAGCUCCAGUGAUCCAUGGGGUGGACGUUAUAAACAGUACAUUAGUUAAAGUUACCUGGUCAACAGUUCCAAAGGACAGAGUACAUGGACGUCUGAAAGGCUAUCAGAUAAAUUGGUGGAAAACAAAAAGUCUGUUGGAUGGAAGAACACAUCCCAAAGAAGUGAACAUUCUAAGAUUUUCAGGACAAAGAAACUCUGGAAUGGUUCCUUCCUUAGAUGCCUUUAGUGAAUUUCAUUUAACAGUCUUAGCCUAUAACUCUAAAGGAGCUGGUCCUGAAAGUGAGCCUUAUAUAUUUCAAACACCAGAAGGAGUACCUGAACAGCCAACUUUUCUAAAGGUCAUCAAAGUUGAUAAAGACACUGCCACUUUAUCUUGGGGACUACCUAAGAAAUUAAAUGGAAACUUAACUGGCUAUCUUUUGCAAUAUCAGAUAAUAAAUGACACCUACGAGAUUGGAGAAUUAAAUGAUAUUAACAUUACAACUCCAUCAAAGCCCAGCUGGCACCUCUCAAACCUGAAUGCAACUACCAAGUACAAAUUCUACUUGAGGGCUUGCACUUCACAGGGCUGUGGAAAACCGAUCACGGAGGAAAGCUCCACCUUAGGAGAAGGGAGUAAAGGUAUCGGGAAGAUAUCAGGAGUAAAUCUUACUCAAAAGACUCACCCAAUAGAGGUAUUUGAGCCGGGAGCUGAACAUAUAGUUCGCCUAAUGACUAAGAAUUGGGGCGAUAAUGAUAGCAUUUUUCAAGAUGUAAUUGAGACAAGAGGGAGAGAAUAUGCUGGUUUAUAUGAUGACAUCUCCACUCAAGGCUGGUUUAUUGGACUGAUGUGUGCGAUUGCUCUUCUCACACUACUAUUAUUAACUGUUUGCUUUGUGAAGAGGAAUAGAGGUGGAAAGUACUCAGUUAAAGAAAAGGAAGAUUUGCAUCCAGACCCAGAAAUUCAGUCAGUAAAAGAUGAAACCUUUGGUGAAUACAGUGACAGUGAUGAAAAGCCUCUCAAAGGAAGCCUUCGGUCCCUUAAUAGGGAUAUGCAGCCUACUGAAAGUGCUGACAGCUUAGUCGAAUACGGAGAGGGAGACCAUGGUCUCUUCAGUGAAGAUGGAUCAUUUAUUGGUGCCUACGCUGGAUCUAAGGAGAAGGGAUCUGUUGAAAGCAAUGGAAGUUCUACAGCAACUUUUCCCCUUCGGGCAUAAACACAACAUAUGUAAGCAACGCUACUGGUUCACCCCAACCUUCCAUAUUUAUCUGUUCAAAGGAGCAAGAACUUUCAUAUAGGAAUAGAAACAUGCUGGCCGAAGAUUUCAUCCAGAAGUCAACAUCCUGCAAUUAUGUUGAAAAGAGUAGUACUUUCUUCAAAAUAUAAAAUGCCAAGCACUUCAGGCCUAUGUUUUGCUUAUAUUGUUUUCAGGUGCUCAAAAUGCAAAACACAAAACAAAUCCUGCAUUUAGAUACACCUCAACUAAAUCCAAAGUCCCCAUUCAGUAUAUUCCAUAUUUGCCUGAUUUUACUAUUCGGUGUGUUUGCAUAGAUGUUGCUACUUGGUGGGUUUUUCUCCGUAUGCACAUUGGUAUACAGUCUCUGAGAACUGGCUUGGUGACUUUGCUUCACUACAGGUUAAAAGACCAUAAGCAAACUGGUUAUUUAAAAUGUAAAAAGGAAUAUGAAAGUCUUAUUAAAACACUUCAUUGAAAAUAUACAGUCUAAAUUUAUUAUUUAAAUUUUACUAGCAAAAGUCUUAGGUGAACAAUCAACUAGUAUUUGUUGAGCUCCUAUUUGCCCAGAGAUGGUCAUAUUUAAACAGAAGUAUACGUUUUUCAGUUUCAACAUGAAUUUUUUUAUUUCUGUCAGUUAUGACAUCCACAAGCAUCACUUUUUGUGUCUGUUUUUUUUUUUUUUCUUGGACUAAAUUCAACUGCAUGGAAGCGGUGGUCAGAAGGUUGUUUUAUACGAGAACAGGCAGAAAGUGCCCAUUGUUCAGGAUUCUAAUAGCUACAUCUACUUAAUAUCUUCAUUUCUAAAUUGACUGCUUUUACCUUUUUCUCAUGUUUAUAUAAUGGUAUGCUUGCAUAUAUUUCAUGAAUACAUUGUACAUAUUAUGUUAAUAUUUACACAAUUUAAAAUAUAGAUGUGUUUUAUUUUGAAGUGAGAAAAUGAACAUUAACAGGCAUGUUUGUACAGCUAGAAUAUAUUAGUAAGAUACUGUUUUUCGUCAUUCCAGAGCUACAACUAAUAACACGAGGUUCCAAAGCUGAAGACUUUGUAUAAAGUAUUUGGGUUUUGUUCUUGUAUUGCUUUCUUUCAACAGUUUCAAAAUAAAAUAUCAUAUAAAUAUUGAGGGAAAUGUUUUCAUAUUUUUCAAAAUAGGUUUUUAUUGUUGAAUGUACAUCUACCCCAGCCCCUCAAAAGAAAAACUGUUUACAUAGAAAUUCCUACACAUACGUUUGCGUAUAUGUUAUUUUAAACAUCUUUGUGGUGAGAAUUUUUUCCCCGAUAUUCUCCUUCUGUCAAAGUCAGAACAAAUUCAGGGAAUUUAUUUUCUGGCAGUUGUGCUCCAGUCCUUUUAAAAUUGUACAUGAACAUGUUUUAGAAACAAUAUGGAGGAUGAUGCAUACAUGUCGGUCAAGUUCAGCGCUCGACAUUUUAUGGAAAGAUUUUUUUAACCUUACCACGAAAUACUUAACUACUGUUUAAGUGAAUUGACUUAUUUCACUUUAGUUUUUGAACUGUGAUUAUUGGUAUACUGUUAUAUCCUCAACUUGGAUUUAUGGUAACCCCUUAUAGUUCAUGGAGACCAAAAUUUGGGGUAUUUAUAAUAGUCAGCGCAGGAAUGCACAUGGAAUAUCUACUUGUCCUUUUGAACCUCACGAGUCAUCCAGAAUGUAUAGACAGGAAAAGCAUGUCUUAUUUAAAACUGUAAUUUAUGGGCUCAGGAUCUGACCGCAGUCCCGGGAGUAAGCAUUUCAAAGGGGGAAGGCAGUGUGGUCCCUACCCUGUGUGAAUGUGAGGAUGUAGACAUCCAUCAGUGCAACUCGAGCUCCAUCCUCCUCCGAUUUCUAAGGUUCCAGUUUUCUGGAGGGACAGUCAUCAUGUUUUGAUUUAUCUGGGAGAAAACUGUGGUGCACAGCUUGUGAGGAGGGCAAGGUUGUGACGUUCGAGCUUAGUUCUGGUGUUAUUCUGUCUCCUCUUCUUUGUCAUCAGCCAAAACGUGGUUUUUAAAGAGAGUCAUGCAGGUUAGAAAUAAUGUCAAAAAUAUUUAGGAAUUUAAUAACCUUUAAGUCAGAAACUAAAACAAAUACUGAAAUAUUAGCUCUUCCUACACUUCGUGUUCCCCUUUAGCUGCCUGAAAAUCAAGAUUGCUCCUGCUCAGAUCUUCUGAGUGGCUAAAACUUAUGGAUAUGAAAAAUGAGAUUGAAUGAUGACUAUGCUUUGCUAUCAUUGUUACCUUUCCUCAAUACUAUUUGGCAACUACUGGGACUCUUCAGCACAAAAGGAAUAGAUCUAUGAUUGACCCUGAUUUUAAUUGUGAAAUUAUAUGAUUCAUAUAUUUUAUGAAUCAGAAUAACCUUCAAAUAAAAUAAAUCUAAGUCGGUUAAAAUGGAUUUCAUGAUUUUCCCUCAGAAAAUGAGUAACAGAGUCCACGGCGUGCAAUGGUAAUUAUAAAUUGGUGAUGCUUGUUUGCAAAUUGCCCACUCGUGAUAAGUCAACAGCCAAUAUUUAAAACUUUGUUCGUUACUGGCUUUACCCUAACUUUCUCUAGUCUACUGUCAAUAUCAUUUUAAUGUAAUUGAUUGUAUAUAGUCUCAAGAAUGGUUGGUGGGCAUGAGUUCCUAGAGAACUGUCCAAGGGUUGGGAAAAUCCAAAUUCUCUUCCUGGUUCCAGCACUGAUUUUGUACAUAAACAUUAGGCAGGUUGCUUAACCUUUUUAUUUCAAACUCUCUCAACUCUAAAGUGCUAAUAAUAAUCUCAGUUACCUUAUCUUUGUCACAGGGUGUUCUUUUUUAUGAAGAAAAAUUUGAAAAUGAUAAAAGCUAAGAUGCCUUCUAACUUCAUAAGCAAACCUUUAACUAAUUAUGUAUCUGAAAGUCACCCCCACAUACCAACUCAACUUUUUUCCUGUGAACACAUAAAUAUAUUUUUAUAGAAAAACAAAUCUACAUAAAAUAAAUCUACUGUUUAGUGAGCAGUAUGAUUUGUACAUGCCAUUGAAAAUUAUUAAUCAGAAGAAAAUUAAGCAGGGUCUUUGCUAUACAAAAGUGUUUUCCACUAAUUUUGCAUGCGUAUUUAUAAGAAAAAUGUGAAUUUGGUGGUUUUAUUCUAUCGGUAUAAAGGCAUUGAUAUUUUAGAUGCACCCGUGUUUGUAAAAAUGUAGAGCACAAUGGAAUUAUGCUGGAAGUCUCAAAUAAUAUUUUUUUCCUAUUUUAUACUCAUGGAAGAGAUAAGCUAAAGAGGGGACAAUAAUGAGAAAUGUUGGUGUGCUUUUCUAAGCAUUUAAAACAUAAUUGCCAAUUGAAACCCUAAAUAUGUUUACAUACCAUUAAGAUAUGAUUCAUGUAACAAUGUUAAAUUAAUUAUAAUGGGAUUGGGUUUGUUAUCUGUGGUAGUAUAUAUCCUAGUGUUCCUAUAGUGAAAUAAGUAGGGUUCAGCCAAAGCUUUCUUUGUUUUGUACCUUAAAUUGUUCGAUUACGUCAUCAAAAGAGAUGAAAGGUAUGUAGAACAGGUUCACGUGAUUACCUUUUUCUUUUGGCUUGGAUUAAUAUUCAUAGUAGAACUUUAUAAAACGUGUUUGUAUUGUAGGUGGUGUUUGUAUUAUGCUUAUGACUAUGUAUGGUUUGAAAAUAUUUUCAUUAUACAUGAAAUUCAACUUUCCAAAUAAAAGUUCUACUUCAUGUAAUCCAAAAA